GCUUCUCCUCAGCGCUCUGGCGCCCCCAACAGGUUCCCAGUGUUCGGCUGGGGCAGGCACGCUGUGGCUGGCUACUUCCCUUCCUCCCAUCCCCCUUGGGCCAAACGGGAUCGGUGCUUCUGGUGAGACGCCUCCCCAUGCACAUCACUCCCAGGUGCCCUAGGGGGCACAUUUCCCACAACUCCCAGAGGGCAGGUUUCUAGAAAGUGCCACCAGUGGGGAGGCGCCACAACUUCACUGCCAUUUUGUGAGGUGCCGCCGUCUCUCCUCCAGCAAGGAAACAAUGACCGAUAAAACAGAGAAGGUGGCUGUAGAUCCUGAAACUGUGUUUAAACGUCCCAGGGAAUGUGACAGUCCUUCGUAUCAGAAAAGGCAGAGGAUGGCCCUGUUGGCAAGGAAACAAGGAGCAGGAGACAGCCUUAUUGCAGGCUCUGCCAUGUCCAAAGAAAAGAAGCUUAUGACAGGACAUGCUAUUCCACCCAGCCAAUUGGAUUCUCAGAUUGAUGACUUCACUGGUUUCAGCAAAGAUGGGAUGAUGCAGAAACCUGGUAGCAAUGCACCUGUGGGAGGAAACGUUACCAGCAGUUUCUCUGGAGAUGACCUAGAAUGCAGAGAAACAGCCUCCUCUCCCAAAAGCCAACGAGAAAUUAAUGCUGAUAUAAAACGUAAAUUAGUGAAGGAACUCCGAUGCGUUGGACAAAAAUAUGAAAAAAUCUUCGAAAUGCUUGAAGGAGUGCAAGGACCUACUGCAGUCAGGAAGCGAUUUUUUGAAUCCAUCAUCAAGGAAGCAGCAAGAUGUAUGAGACGAGACUUUGUUAAGCACCUUAAGAAGAAACUGAAACGUAUGAUUUGAGAAUACUUGUCCCUGGAGGAUUAUCACACCCCAAAUGCAUAAUCUCGUUAAUGAUUGAGGAGAGAAAAGGAUCAGAUUGCUGUUUUCUACAAUGGAGCAGGAUAUUGCUGAAGUCUCCUGGCAUAUGUUACCGAAUCAACUGGCCUUCCAGAGGCUAAGAAAUUUCUGUUAGUAAAAGAUGUUCUUUUUCCCAAAGCGUUUUAUUUGAAAGGA